ACUACUGCCAGGUCUCUCUGCUCUUGGUGUCUGCAUCCAGGGCUGGGAGGGGGUCAAAUGUAUCACACUAUCGGCCCCAGGCCCACCAAGCCUGGGGAGGUGGCCACCCUUCCAUGAUGGCAUUUGGAUGUUCCCUGUGUGUGGGGAGGGCACGGGGACUCCAUUCAUAGACCACCUCUGGGACAGUGUGUCUGCCUCUGAGGUCAGACGCUCUGCACUGGGACAGCGUGGAGUGGAGGGAAACCAAGCUUGGGGCUCAUUGGAGGGGCUUGCUGGCAGACACCGCCCUUUGUGGGAAACUGACUGUGGGAGAGGGGAACCCCAACCUCUGUCACCACAUCCCUCUUCCCUGUUGUCACACCUGUCACCUGCUGCCGUAGCCAUGAGACUUCCCAAGGGUCACUGCUGCCACUCACUGCACAGCCUGGAAGGGAGUCCACAGGGGACAUACAGUGAGCAAGAGACCUGUGCCACUCAGGCCUCCUGGGGGUGUCCCCAGUGCAGCCAUGAUGAUAAUCACAGCUACCAUUCACCAAGCCCUGCCCACAGUCUAACCUACUCUAUUCACAACACUCCCAGCAGCAAGGCAAGUGAGGUGCUGCCGUCAUCCAGGCUGGACAGUUCAGUGAUUUGCCUGAGGCCCCACAGCAGGAGAACGAGAAGGCUGCCUGAUCAGAGAGUCUCUGAAGAAGAUUCUGUGGCUACAGGCUUCAGCAGAGUGUGAGGGAGACCCCGGUUAUUUCCUCAGCUGUUUCCACCAAAUCCUCCUGUCUUUCGUGGCCAACACCCCAGGCAAGGCUUGGGGCCCCCGUCUGCUGCUGGACGCAGAGCCAUGAAGAAGAAGUUAGUGGUGCUGGGCCUGCUGGCCGUGGUCCUGGUGCUGGUCAUUGUCAGCCUCUGUCUCUGGCUGCCCUCGGCCUCCAAGGAACCUGACAACCAUGUGUACACCAGGGCUGCCGUGGCCGCGGAUGCCAAGCAGUGCUUGGAGAUUGGGAGGGACACACUGCGGGACGGUGGCUCUGCAGUGGAUGCAGCCAUUGCAGCCCUGUUGUGUGUGGGGCUCAUGAAUGCCCACAGCAUGGGCAUCGGGGUUGGCCUCUUCCUCACCAUCUACAACAGCACCACUCAUGAGUCUGAGGUCAUCAAUGCCCGCGAGGUGGCCCCCAGGCUGGCCUUUGCCAGCAUGUUCAACAGCUCGGAGCAGUCCCAGAAGGGAGGGCUGUCGGUGGCGGUGCCUGGGGAGAUCCGAGGCUAUGAGCUGGCACACCAGCGGCAUGGGCGGCUGCCCUGGGCUCGCCUCUUCCAGCCCAGCAUCCAGCUGGCCCGCCAGGGCUUCCCCGUGGGCAAGGGCUUGGCGGCAGUCCUGGAAAACAAGCGGACCGUCAUCGAGCAGCAGCCUGUCUUGUGUGAGGUGUUCUGCCGGGAUAGAAAGGUGCUUUGGGAGGGGGAGAGACUGACCCUGCCGCGGCUGGCUGACACCUACGAGAUGCUGGCCAUCGAGGGUGCCCAGGCCUUCUACAACGGCAGCCUCAUGGCCCAGAUUGUGAAGGACAUCCAGGCGGCUGGGGGCAUUGUGACAGCUGAGGACCUGAACAACUACUGUGCUGAGCUGAUCGAGCACCCGCUGAACAUCAGCCUGGGAGACGCGGUGCUGUACAUGCCCAGUGCGCGGCUCAGCGGGCCCGUGCUGGCCCUCAUCCUCAACAUCCUCAAAGGGUACAACUUCUCCCGGGAGAGCGUGGAGACCCCCGAGCAGAAGGGCCUGACGUACUACCGCAUCGUAGAGGCUUUCCGGUUUGCCUACGCCAAGAGGACCCUGCUUGGGGACCCCAAGUUUGUGGAUGUGACUGAGGUGGUCCGCAACAUGACCUCUGAGUUCUUCACUGCCCAGCUCCGGUCCCAGAUCUCUGACCACACCACUCACCCGAUCUCCUACUACAAGCCCGAGUUCUACACGCCGGAUGACGGGGGCACUGCUCACCUGUCUGUCGUCGCAGAGGACGGCAGUGCUGUGUCCGCCACCAGCACCAUCAACCUCUACUUUGGCUCCAAGGUCUGCUCCCCGGUCAGUGGGAUCCUGUUCAAUAAUGAAUGGACGACUUCAGCUCUCCCAGCAUUCACCAAUGAGUUUGGGGCACCCCCCUCACCUGCCAAUUUCAUCCAGCCAGGGAAGCAGCCGCUCUUGUCCAUGUGCCCGACGAUCAUGGUGGGCCAGGACGGCCAGGUCCGGAUGGUGGUGGGAGCUGCUGGGGGCACGCAGAUCACCACAGACACUGCACUGGCCAUCAUCUACAACCUCUGGUUCGGCUAUGACGUGAAGAGGGCCGUGGAGGAGCCCCGGCUGCACAACAAGCUUCUGCCCAACGUCACGACAGUGGAGAGAAACAUUGACCAGGCAGUGACUGCAGCCCUGGAGACCCGGCACCAUCACACCCAGAUCGCGUCCACCUUCAUCGCUGUGGUGCAAGCCAUCGUCCGCACGGCUGGUGGCUGGGCAGCUGCCUCGGACUCCAGGAAAGGCGGGGAACCUGCUGGCUACUGAGUGCUCCAGGCAGACAAGGCUGACAAGCAAUCCAGGGACAAGAUACUCACCAGGAUGAGGAAGAGGACUUUGGGGGACGGGCUUCCCCUGUGAGCAGCAGAGCAGCAUAAUAAAUGAGGCCACUGUGCCAGGCUCCAGGUGGCCUCCCUGGCCUGUCUCCCCA